AUCUGCCACGAUGUUGCUGCUCAGCCUGACCCUAAGCCUGGUUCUCCUCGGCUCCUCCUGGGGCUGCGGCAUUCCUGCCAUCAAACCGGCACUGAGCUUCAGCCAGAGGAUUGUCAACGGGGAGAAUGCAGUGUUGGGCUCCUGGCCCUGGCAGGUGUCCCUGCAGGACAGCAGCGGCUUCCACUUCUGCGGUGGUUCUCUCAUCAGCCAGUCCUGGGUGGUCACUGCUGCCCACUGCAAUGUCAGCCCUGGCCGCCAUUUUGUUGUCCUGGGCGAGUAUGACCGAUCAUCAAACGCAGAGCCCUUGCAGGUUCUGUCCGUCUCUCGGGCCAUUACACACCCUAGCUGGAACUCUACCACCAUGAACAAUGACGUGACGCUGCUGAAGCUCGCCUCGCCAGCCCAGUACACAACACGCAUCUCGCCAGUUUGCCUGGCAUCCUCAAACGAGGCUCUGACUGAAGGCCUCACGUGUGUCACCACCGGCUGGGGUCGCCUCAGUGGCGUGGGCAAUGUGACACCAGCACAUCUGCAGCAGGUGGCUUUGCCCCUGGUCACUGUGAAUCAGUGCCGGCAGUACUGGGGCUCAAGUAUCACUGACUCCAUGAUCUGUGCAGGUGGCGCAGGUGCCUCCUCGUGCCAGGGUGACUCCGGAGGCCCUCUUGUCUGCCAGAAGGGAAACACAUGGGUGCUUAUUGGUAUUGUCUCCUGGGGCACCAAAAACUGCAAUGUGCGCGCACCUGCUGUGUAUACUCGAGUUAGCAAGUUCAGCACCUGGAUCAACCAGGUCAUAGCCUACAACUGAGCUCACCACAGGCCCUCCCCAGCUCAACCCAUUAAAGACCCAGGCCCUGUCCCAUCAUGCAUUCAUGUCUGUCUUCCUGGCUCAGGAGAAAGAAGAGGCUGUUGAGGGUCCGACUCCCUACUUGGACUUCUGGCACAGAAGGGGCUGAGUGACUCCUUGAGUAGCAGUGGCUCUUCCUAGAGUAGCCAUGCCGAGGCCGGGGCCCCCACCCCUCCUCCAGGGCAACCCCUUGGUCCUACAGCAAGAAGCCAGAACUGUUGGAAUGAAUGGCAGCCCUCCCUGGAGAGGCAGCCUGUUUACUGAAUACAGAGGAUACGUUUACAAACUGAAUACGCAUAAUAAAUAACUGCACAUUCUCCA